AAAGCCAGCGAAGCACGGGCCCAACCGGGCCAUGUCGGGGGAGCCUGAGCUCAUUGAGCUGCGGGAGCUGGCACCCGCUGGGCGCGCUGGGAAGGGCCGCACCCGGCUGGAGCGUGCCAACGCGCUGCGCAUCGCGCGGGGCACCGCGUGCAACCCCACACGGCAGCUGGUCCCUGGCCGUGGCCACCGCUUCCAGCCCGCGGGGCCCGCCACGCACACGUGGUGCGACCUCUGUGGCGACUUCAUCUGGGGCGUCGUGCGCAAAGGCCUGCAGUGCGCGCGCCUCUCUGCAGAUUGCAAGUUCACCUGCCACUACCGCUGCCGCGCGCUCGUCUGCCUGGACUGUUGCGGGCCCCGGGACCUGGGCUGGGAACCCGCGGUGGAGCGGGACACGAACGUGGACGAGCCUGUGGAGUGGGAGACACCUGACCUUUCUCAAGCUGAGAUUGAGCAGAAGAUCAAGGAGUACAAUGCCCAGAUCAACAGCAACCUCUUCAUGAGCUUGAACAAGGACGGUUCUUACACAGGCUUCAUCAAGGUUCAGCUGAAGCUGGUGCGCCCUGUCUCUGUGCCCUCCAGCAAGAAGCCACCCUCCUUGCAGGAUGCCCGGCGGGGCCCAGGACGGGGCACAAGUGUCAGGCGCCGCACUUCCUUUUACCUGCCCAAGGAUGCUGUCAAGCACCUGCAUGUGCUGUCACGCACAAGGGCACGUGAAGUCAUUGAGGCCCUGCUGCGAAAGUUCUUGGUGGUGGAUGACCCCCGCAAGUUUGCACUCUUUGAGCGCGCUGAGCGUCACGGCCAAGUGUACUUGCGGAAGCUGUUGGAUGAUGAGCAGCCCCUGCGGCUGCGGCUCCUGGCAGGGCCCAGUGACAAGGCCCUGAGCUUUGUCCUGAAGGAAAAUGACUCUGGGGAGGUGAACUGGGACGCCUUCAGCAUGCCUGAACUACAUAACUUCCUACGUAUCCUGCAGCGGGAGGAGGAGGAGCACCUCCGCCAGAUCCUGCAGAAGUACUCCUAUUGCCGCCAGAAGAUCCAAGAGGCCCUGCACGCCUGCCCCCUUGGGUGACCUCUUGUACCCCCAGGUGGAAGGCAGACAGCAGGCAGCGCCAAGUGCGUGCCGUGUGAGUGUGACAGGGCCAGUGGGGCCUGUGGAAUGAGUGUGCAUGGAGGCCCUCCUGUGCUGGGGGAAUGAGCCCAGAGAACAGCGAAGUAGCUUGCUCCCUGUGUCCACCUGUGGGUGUAGCCAGGUAUGGCUCUGCACCCCUCUGCCCUCAUUACUGGGCCUUAGUGGGCCAGGGCUGCCCUGAGAAGCUGCUCCAGGCCUGCAGCAGGAGUGGUGCAGACAGAAGUCUCCUCAAUUUUUGUCUCAGAAGUGAAAAUCUUGGAGACCCUGCAAACAGAACAGGGUCAUGUUUGCAGGGGUGACGGCCCUCAUCUAUGAGGAAAGGUUUUGGAUCUUGAAUGUGGUCUCAGGAUAUCCUUAUCAGAGCUAAGGGUGGGUGCUCAGAAUAAGGCAGGCAUUGAGGAAGAGUCUUGGUUUCUCUCUACAGUGCCAACUCCUCACACACCCUGAGGUCAGGGAGUGCUGGCUCACAGUACAGCAUGUGCCUUAAUGCUUCAUAUGAGGAGGAUGUCCCUGGGCCAGGGUCUGUGUGAAUGUGGGCACUGGCCCAGGUUCAUACCUUAUUUGCUAAUCAAAGCCAGGGUCUCUCCCUCAGGUGUUUUUUAUGAAGUGCGUGAAUGUAUGUAAUGUGUGGUGGCCUCAGCUGAAUGCCUCCUGUGGGGAAAGGGGUUGGGGUGACAGUCAUCAUCAGGGCCUGGGGCCUGAGAGAAUUGGCUCAAUAAAGAUUUCAAGAUCC